AUCCUCGGCGACGCCGUAUGGCUUCCAGGGCGAGGCCAUGUACCGGGUGCCCGAGUUUUAUGCGAGGAGGAAGCGGUUAGGUGGGCAGACCCCUUACUUGAUGGAUCAGUUGGGAUUACGAUUAGGGAUGUGGUACUGGAAAGAUGAAACCAGAACUCUUGAAUUCAGAAGAUGAAGAAACAAGGCUCAGGGAGAUUAAGCAACUGAACCAAAGUCAUACAGCCAGUUUGCCGCAGAAGAUUCUGUCCAGUGGCUCCUGAAACAUCACCCUCAUUUUACACCUGCAGCAGAAGUCAAGGAAAAAGGAAAGAAAGGCAAAGCAGUUCACUUUGCAGAAACUGAUGGUCCAGCUUCAGACAGGUUGACAGAUAAAAGACUUGCUGCAAAAGAUGAUAAGUCAGCUAAAGCUGUAGAGAAACGAGGUCAACAGGGCACCAUUACACUGGAUGAUGUUAAAUUUGUUACUUUGCUUUUGCUACAAGAUACUGAGAUGCAGCGGAUCUGUUCUUUUACAACAUUUAUGAGGAAUAAGAAUCUUGAUAAUUUCCUCAUGGCAUUAUUGUACUACUUAUCCCAUUACUUGGAAAAAAACUCACUGGAAAAGAAACCCAAAAGCUAUAUGGUAGGCCUUGUAGAGAAAAAAGAAAUGGAAUUGGUUUUAAGUGAAUUAGAAGCAGCACAGAGGUACUUGGCGCAGAAGUACUGUAUCCUUGUGCUGGGCUUGGCCGUGCCGGAUAAGCAUCACAUGUGCUGUGGAAAGGAGAAAAUAUCAGAUACACAGAAAGACUGGAAGUUCUUUGAGUCCUUUUAUACUUUCUGUACAUAUGUGGCUUGGAUUGUCUUCCGACGUCAACACUUGACAGAGAUUGAAGAAGAAGUAGGGAGACUCUUUCGUACCAAUAUGUUCAACAUUCCUCGCAGGAGGCGUGAAGAUGAGGAAUCAGGAGGGGAAAAGAAACGCAUGACUUUUGUUCAGUUCAGGAGAAUGAUGGCAAAACGCCCAGCAAUUAAAAAAGCUAUCAACAUGCGUUCUCCAGUCAUGUCUACUCUGCUGCCAUCUCUCAGAGAAAAAGCUCAAAACGUCUUUGAGAAAAAGUAUCAUCAAGUAGACGUCAGAUUCCCAGCCGAGAUGCAAAAGCAUGUGGGAACUCUGGACUCUGUGCCCAUGCCGGUAGUUGGCAUCUUGGGGGAGCCUCGAUGUCUAUUCAACCCACAUACGCUUCACCCCCUUGAUCCAGAAGAAAACACAAAAUCAUUUGGGAGAUAUCCUUCCUUGAUGGAAAACAAUAACAUGAGGAUUCAGGAUACACUGGACUUGGUCAUGAAAACACUGUCCUCUCAUACAUCAUGCCCUAAGUAACCUGGUACAUUCCAUAUCUCAAGUAAACUACUUUGACUUUAUA